ACUGGACUCUGAAACGGGCAUGUACAGAGAAGAGGAGACCCCAACACGCUUCAAGCUUUGAGUGGAGAGGACACAGCCUCUGCUGGGACAGGGAACAGAGGGAUGCGGAGACCCUGAAGAUGCUUUUGGACAGUGGUCUGAGGUUGGGACAGUGGCAGGAGAUACCAUUCACCCAGGAUCUCCAGGACAAGAGAUCAGCCUGGCAGUUACAUGUGUUUUUUUUCAAACUGGUUGCCAGGUUGGCAUGAGCGAUGACAUCAGAGAUUCCGACCUUCCUGAUUGGAGGGACCGGACUCUGUCGGCAUCUGGGAGUUCAGUUGGACAACAGUAACUUCUCAGAGCUGUUCUCCACUCCUGACUUCUCCCAGCCUCGAGAAUUGAUAACACACUCUUCUGGAUCCCAGCAGUGUCCAGAAGAAGACCAAGGACAGAACAGAGACUAGGUUUGGUGAGAUGGGACAGAUUUUGGGAAAGAUCAUGAUGAGCCAUCAACCGCAGCCCCAGGAAGAGCGGAGCCCCCAGCGGAGCACCUCAGGGUACCCCCUCCAGGAGGUGGUGGAUGAUGAAGUGUUGGGACCAUCAGCCCCUGGGGUAGAUCCCAGCCCCCCACGUAGGUCCCUUGGCUGGAAAAGGAAGAGGGAAUGUUUGGAUGAAUCUGAUGAUGAGCCAGAGAAGGAGCUCGCCCCUGAGCCUGAGGAGACCUGGGUGGCGGAGACGCUGUGUGGCCUCAAGAUGAAGGCGAAGCGACGGCGAGUGUCGCUCGUGCUCCCUGAGUACUACGAGGCCUUCAACAGGCUGCUUGAGGAUCCUGUCAUUAAAAGACUCCUGGCCUGGGACAAAGAUCUGAGGGUGUCGGACAAGUAUCUCCUGGCUAUGGUCAUAGCGUAUUUCAGCCGGGCCGGCCUCCCCUCCUGGCAAUACCAACGCAUUCAUUUCUUCCUGGCUCUCUAUCUGGCCAAUGACAUGGAGGAGGACGACGAGGCCCCCAAACAAAACAUCUUCUACUUCCUGUACGAGGAGACCCGCUCUCAUAUACCCUUGCUCAGUGAGCUUUGGUUCCAGUUAUGCCGUUACAUGAACCCGAGGGCCAGGAAGAACUGCUCUCAGAUAGCCUUGUUCCGGAAGUAUCGGUUCCACUUCUUUUGUUCCAUGCGCUGCAGGGCUUGGGUUUCCCUGGAGGAGUUGGAAGAGAUCCAGGCUUAUGACCCAGAGCACUGGGUGUGGGCGCGAGAUCGCGCCCACCUUUCCUAGAGCUCCAGGGACCGUGGAGGCCUGAGGUCAUCGGCCUGAGAGAAGGUACAUCUGCAUCCUCCGGGGUAAAGGCAGAAUAUUGGGGUCUAUUUCGGAAAUCCAAGGAACCCAAUUGCUUGAUCUGGCUUCAAGCCUGGGCAACGUGGCGAGAUCCCCUCUCCACAAAAAUACAAAAAUUAGCCAGGCGAUGUGGGAGGCAUCUCUACUCCCAACUACUCAGGAGGCUGAGGCGGGAGGAUCGCUGGAGCCUGGGAGGUCGGGGCUGCAGGGAGCCCUGAUCCUGCCACUGCACUCCAGCCCGGGCGACAGAGUGAGACCCUGCCUCAAAAAUAAUCAUAAAUACUGAGUUCGGGGAGGUUCAUUAUGAUUGAUGCACUUGAGUUACCGAUUUGGGUCGAGGGUUCAGUGAAGCUUUGGUUUACAUCUUGUGCAGCUAACCAUGUUGAGCACAGAGCAUGAGACUUCGUCAUGAGGAGGGAGGAUUAUGGAUUAGGCUUCUGGACUCGUGGUUCGUGAUGUUGUCACGUUAGAAACAGAUCUAGCACGGUUACAAGUUUAGAUCUGAAGUGACACAAAAGGCCCCAGCUGUGAUGAAGUCCAAAGCCACAUUCUCUGAGGGUGCCCUACUCCCUGGGAAGACCCACCCAAAGUCCUGGCUAUGAAGCAGAUCACUGGGGCUGACCUUGGGUGUAUUAAGUUUUGGAGUCAGGGUCACCAAAGUGUGAGUUUCACAGUUGAACACGAUGGUUCAGAAGCAGGGUAUAGAAUGAAAGGCAGGAGAUAAAAUUGCACUUCUCAAUUGCUCUGAACUCUAGCUAGACUUGACAUGGGACGUGAAUAACCUUCCUGUCUAGAGAGCUGCCUCCUUCAAGUGUGACAUUGUCUCUCUCACUUCCAGAACACCGGACCCAGGGGAGAUGUGGAUUUUCAGCAGGAACUUUAUUCCAAUGCUAAUGGCAGACAUCAGGAAGGAGGAGAGGAACCAUUUGUGCAGAUCAUCUAGAAGAACCUGGACCAUUCUUGACAGAGCUGAAUACAGUGAUCACGUUGUCCUCCAAGGAGCAGGGGUGGGGUGGGGUACUUCUAGGAGUCCUUGGAGAAAAGUAAGAAACCAGGAGUGUUUCCAGUUCCACCCUUUCCUGCGGCACCACCUCCCUUUUUAUAUUGCUGAAUGCCAACCUCCCUGGGGCGGAACCUGGAGGUCCUGUUUCUUAUGGACUUGGUUGCCACAGUCCAGGAGCAUUUGAAGGCACAGUGCAGGGGCUCAGAUUGGCACAGAAUUCUUUGUGAAAUAUGAGUGCCACAGACUGUAACAGAUAGCUUCAUGCACACUAUGCAUUUUAUUGGUUUGUUUGGAAAAUGUUGGCCAUUGAAUUAUUAAUAGGUUUAUUUCAAAUAGUUUGGAAAUUGUUGUACUUUUGAAAACAUGCUGUUCCUGUAGAGUUUUUUGAUGAGAGUUAUAGUUGUUAUAUAUACCUAAAGAUAAUUUUCUUUUCAUUUUUAAGUGAGAAUUCUUUUUAUCCUAAAUCUUUUAUUAUCUUUAAUUUUUUUUCUGUAUUAUUAUAUGUGCUCCUGAAGCGAGCACUCUUUUUAUCUAUGAUACUUCCAUAAUAAUCUCUUCUAUUUAUAGCUAUUGGUAGUUCCCCACCAGAAAAAAACAUAAUUCUGGUGAUAGAAAUUUUUAUUUGCUGUUUAGGUUUGUGACUGACUUGUGAGAAUUCAGUUGUGAUUUUUAACAUGUCUCAGAUAUAUAUACUAACACGUCUAAUAUAUACUAUCUAUUUUAUUGGUUUAUUUUGAAAAACAUGGGUAUAGAAUUAUUUAAAUAUUAUUUUAUUUACUGAAAUAUUUAUUAAAUAUAUUUAUUUAUUUAAAUAUUAUUAUUACUUUAAAUAUUAUUUUAAAUAUUUUGGAAAUACUGGUAUUUUUGAAUAGAUGCUGUUUCUAUAAAGCUGUGUGAUGGGUAUUAUAACUGUUGUAUACACAUACAUAUAAUUUUGUUUUCCUUUUUAAGAGAGGAUUCUUUUCAUCCUAAAUCUUUUACCUUUCAAUCUUUGUAUCUAUUAUUACACGUGCUGCUGAAGGGAGCAUGGUUUUUAUCUAUGAUACUUAGUUAACAUAUAUAUUACAUUUAUAGCUAUGUGGUAGUUCCCCUAAAUUCUUGUAAAAAUAAAUUUUUAUUUGAUAUUUAGUGUAUGUUUGAAAUGUGAGAAUUCAGAUGGAAUUUUUUAUCUUGUUUUGGCAUGUUUGUAUGUUACUUUAAAGAGGAUGUGUGUUCUAAAGGAGGACAUGAGCUGUGUGUUUUCAAGAGAACAGUGCAGUGCAUCUCUUGGGGAAACAUAAUAAAGAUGAACUUUUCUCACCUUCACAGUGAGUGUGAUCAUAUUGUGGUCUGGAUUGAUUAUUUGCUGUCAAGUGACAUUUUUCCUUAAUGGGGUUGUGGUUAUUUGAACAUAUUUAUUAGCUUUGGAAGAUAAUCCUGUGCUGUUUUUUAUGUAGAAAAAAACAUACGGCUGGGUGCAGUGCUCACACCUACAAUCCCAGCAGUUUUGGAGGUCAUGGCGGGAGGAUCACUUGAAGCCUAUUUUUAAUUUUUAUUUUUUAAAGAAAAACAACAGAAGAGAAGGCUGAUCCCAAGCUACAGGGUUUUUUUGUUUGUUUGUUUGUUUGUUUGUUUUGGAGACAGUCUCGCUCUGUCUCCCAGGCUGGAGUGCAGUGGCACAACCUCGGCUCCCUGCAACUUUCACCUCCGCGUUCAAGCAAAUUCUCCUGCCUCAGCCUCCCAAGUAGCUGGGACUACAGGCAUCCGCCUGUACGUCUGACUAACUUUUGUAAAAAUAGUAGAGACAAGGUUUCACCAUGUUGGCCAGGCUGGUCUCAAACUCCUGACCUCAAGUGAUCCACCCGCCUCAGUCUCCCAAAGUGCUGGGAUUAUAGGCAUGAGCUACUGUGCCCAGACCCCAAGCUAGAGUUUUAAAGCAGGAAAUGAGAGAAAGAUAUUGAGAGAGGAAAACCAGGUGGUAAGAAAACUCUAAAGGUGGCUGGGCGUGGUGGCUCACGCCUGUGAUCCCAGCAGGAGUUCGAGACCAGGCAGGAGAAUCACUAGCAGAGAAUAUGUCUCCCCAACCCCUCUCAAAAAAAAAAAAAAAGUCCAGGCGCGGUGGCUCAGGACUGUAAUCCCAGCACUUUGGGAGGCUGAGGUGGGUGGAUCAUGAGGUCAGGAGAUCAAGACCAUCCUGGCUAAUACGGUGAAACCCCAUCUCUGCUAAAAAUACAAAAAAUUAGCUGGGCGCGGUGGCAGGCGCCUGUAGUCCCAGCUACUCCGGAGGCUGAGGCAGGAGAAUGGUGUGAACCCAGGAGGCGGAGCCUGCAGUGAGCAGAGAUCGCGCCACUGCACUCCAGCCUGGGUGAAAGCGCGAGACUCCAUCACAAAAGAAAAAAAAAAAAAGAAAGUUCCUGCAACAGUUCAAGCUGUGAAAGACAGGCACUCUGCCAUGCAAUUCUUUGUGAUUUUUCUUUUUUAUUUUUGGAGUCGGGGUCUUGUGCUGUCACCCAGACUGGGGUGCAGUGGUGCGGUCAUAGCUCACUGUGGGCUCAGACUCAAGCUCAAGCAAUCUUCUUAUCUUGCCUUUCUAAUUGCUGGGAUUAUAAGCAUGAGCCACUGCACCUGGCCUGUGUGACGUAAUUCUGAUGUCAACUCCCUGAUGUUACAUCAAAUGCCACAGGUUAAGGCCACCAGCCCCCGCUAGGCUGCCCUCGCUUCAGAUGCAGCUGCAAGCUUGGGUGUCCACAGACCGCAUGUACUUCUCACCAACUGGCUGCAAAUUUGGAGGUUCCCACCACGUCCUCAGGUUUGAUAAUUCACCAUAACAACCCACAGAACUCUGAAAAGCAUGAUACUUUCUCUUUCUUUAUUUGAGACAGAGUCUUGCUCUGUCACCCAGGCUGGAGUGCAGUGGCCACCAUGCUUGGCUAAUUUUAGUAUUUGUAUUAGAGACAGGGUUUCGCCAUGUGGGCCAGGCUGGUCUUGAACUCCUGACCUCAGGUGAUCCACCCACCUUGGCCUCCCAAAGUGCUGGGAUUACAGGCAUAGCCACUGUGCCUGGCUGACUUCUAGAGUUUCAAUAACAGAGAUGUGGUUCAAGAAGAAAAGGGAGACAUGUUUUGUAGACAGCAGGAGCUUCAUGAAAAGAAGCCAAUGAAGGGCAGGAUGUGUAGCUGUCUACCUACAGGAAACCAGCCAGGAGCCUCCCCACAGGGACUUCAGCACAGAUGGCCGGGAAAAUCUGCAUUCACCUGAGCUCUGGACCUAAGAGAGGACAAGGCCUUGACUGUUUCUACAGACUCACAAGAUGCAAUCUCUGCGGUCCAUGCCCGUGGUGUGAUCUGGGAAACAGGGGGCCUUCUAAAUGCCAACAACAAGGAAAUCAAAUGUGCAACAGACAGAAAUAUCGGCAUUGACACGGGCCAUGGAGAGGCCUAAACAGAUGACUGCAGUCCACUGCCAAGGUCAUCAAAGGGGUGACUCUGAAAUAAGAAAUUUCAGACGCCACGGCCCAAAUAGCUGCACGAGGUGGGGAAGUCCUCCACAUGCCUCUGCUUCCUUCAGUACCUCUUCAUGAAAUAAGCCGAGGUACUUCCCUGGGGAAUUUCCUUUCUCUUUCUUUCUUUCGAGACGGAGUCUU